AGUGGGACGCCAAGACUGGAGAGGAAGCGACUGCGGGGAGUAUUUCCAUUUUAACCGGAAACAAUCCCUGAACCCACAGGAAUGAAUGCCUAAUGGUGGAGUUUCAGCCAUCAGUGACAGGCUGAACCCAGACUCCCAGGGCACCUGCUUGCACCUUUGAAUGAUGGCCUGAACUAUGAACAAACGGGACUAUAUGAACACUUCGGUACAGGAGCCCCCUCUUGACUACUCCUUCAGAAGCAUCCACGUCAUUCAAGAUCUGGUAAAUGAGGAGCCAAGGACAGGACUACGACCACUGAAGCGUUCAAAGUCGGGGAAAUCACUGACCCAGUCCCUGUGGCUGAAUAACAAUGUUCUCAAUGAUCUGAGAGACUUCAACCAGGUGGCUUCACAGCUGUUGGAGCACCCAGAGAACCUGGCCUGGAUCGACCUGUCCUUUAAUGACCUGACUUCCAUUGACCCUGUCCUAACAACUUUCUUCAACCUGAGUGUCCUCUAUCUUCACGGCAACAGCAUCCAGCGCCUGGGGGAGGUGAAUAAGCUGGCUGUCCUUCCUCGGCUCCGUAGCCUGACACUCCAUGGGAACCCCAUGGAGGAAGAGAAAGGGUAUAGGUAAGUGCCCUGCCCCUGGAGGUAGCGUCUAGCUGGGCUCCCCUAAAGGAAAGGAGGAGGAGAAACAAGAAAUCUACGACCAUUCUUCUGCCAUGCUUGGACCUGGGAAGGGAGUAACAGACCUCUAAGCAUUCCUUGCUCUCAGUCAGGAUAAACCUAAUCUUUCCCAAACUAUGCUCAAGUCCCUCCAUUCCUUGCAGUCAGGGAAGACAACAGCAACUAGUGGAGGGGGAAGGGGAUUCUGGUGGGGGUGCUGGCCCCCAGCCUAAGUCUUCCCCACAGGCAAUAUGUGCUGUGCACCCUGUCCCGUAUCACCACGUUCGACUUCAGUGGGGUCACCAAAGCAGACCGCACCACAGCUGAAGUCUGGAAACGCAUGAACAUCAAGCCCAAGAAGGCCUGGACCAAGCAGAAUACACUUUGAGGCUCCCACGACCCUAGUAGUCCUAAAGGCCUAAGCAUAGACAGCAUGGUUUGACAAUAAAUAAUUUGAGCUGUUGAGCAGAUGAGAAGUCACUUACACCUUGUAGAGAUGUUCUCUAACUCAGGCAACUGCAAGUAGCUCUAGCCUUUUCUUUUCUUUUUUUUUUUUUUGAGACGGAGUCUCACUCUGUCACACAGGCUGGAGUGCAGUGGCACGAUCUUGGCUCACUGCAACCUCAGCCUCCCAGGUUCAAGAGAUUCUCCUGCCUCAGCCUCCCCAGUAGCUGUGAUUAAAGGCGCCUGCCACCAUGACUGGCUAAUUUUGUUGUUGUUGUUGUUGUUUUGAGACGGUUUCACUCGUCACCCCAGCUGGAGUGCAGUGGUGCGAUCUCAGCUCACUGCAACCUCCGCCUGCUGGGUUCAAGCGAUUCUCCUGCCUCAGCCUCCUGAGUAGCUGGGAUUACAGGCGCCUGCUACCACAUCCAGCUAAUUUUUUUUUUUGAGACGGAGUCUCGCUCUGUCACCCAGGCUGGAGUGCAGUGGCACGAUCUCGGCUCACUGCAAACUCCGCCUUCCAGGUUCACGCCAUUCUCCUGCCUCAGCCUCCCAAGUAGCUGGGACUAUAGGCACCUACUACCACGCCUGGCUAAUUUUUUGUAUUUUUAGUAGAGACGGGGUUUCACCAUGUUAGCCAGGAUGGUCUCCAUCUCCUGACCUUGUGAUCCACCCACCUCGGCUUCCCCCAGCUAAUUUUUUAUAUUUUAGUAGAGACAAGGUUUCGCCAUGUUGGCCAGGCUGGUCUUGAACUCCUGACCUCAGGUGAUCCGUCUGCUUUGGCCUCCCAAAGUGCUGGGAUUAGAAGCGUGAGCCACCACGCCCAGCCUUUUUUUGUAUUUUUAGUAGAGAUGGGGUUUCGCCAUGUUGGCCAGGCUGGUCUCAAACUCCUGACCUCAGGUGAUCUGCCCACCUCAGCCUCCCAAAGUGCUAGGAUUACAGGAUAAGCCACUGCACCUGGCCAGCUCUAGUCUUAUUUUGCUGAAAAAGGGAGGCAAUUGAGGGAAAGGCCUGCUGGCCUGGGACACUGGAGACGUGGGUUUACCACACAGCCUUGGGAAAUUUAUCUAACUCUCUGGGCCCCUUUGUACUUUUCAGCUUAGAGAUUUGGGGGUUAAAGUAGAUCAGUAAUUUCCAAACUCUUCACAGAGUACCAGGGUCUGUAGAGAUGCCUCACAGGCCUCCAUGACAGGCCAAGAAGAUGGCCUAUGAUCUCUGAAACCAGCCCCCACUUCAAUCAGAUCAAAGUAAUUCCAUUCUGUUUUAUAUGCUGGGAUUCUGCUUAAGAUUUCAUUUGAUAAAAAGAAUCUUCUGCUUAAAAA